AGAGGUUCUCGGACGCCCUCCGGCGAAGCCACCUGUUGAUGCUUUUGACUUUCUGUCCUUGUUCCUCGUCCCAUCUGGAGCAUUUCCAAUUCUGGUUUUGCGGAGCAGCAGGUCUGAGCUUGUCCGGCGAGGGUGGGAGUUGGUCCCGGCGGAGAUCCAGUGGGAAGAGCCGGCGGCUGCCCGGGCGUCUCCUUGAGCCUCCAGAGGACUCACAACACUCCGGGGCAUGUUGCUCUUUCAAAUACCAGGAAUGGACUCUGGGGAAUGGGGCACCCUUGAAGUCUGAUUAUUUCUUCCCUGUAGAGCCCCAGGGGCUAAUUAAACUCGUGUUUAUGGACUCCAAUGCCUCCUUGCCUUUAAUUCAGUAUAAUCCUACCAACAUUUAUUGAGCUUCUCUGGGCCAGGCAGAGUUCUGGGUGCCGAGGACAUAGAAAUGGAUCUAAACUUGGUUCUUGUCCCCAUAACCUCACAAUGUGGUUGAGGAAGACUCAGCAGUUACCUACACAGGUAACUUCGAGUCAAGGCAGUUUAGACAAGAUCCACUGACAGCCUGACUGGAGGAAGCCUGUGGGCCAUGGUGGGGCAGUUAUGACACCAUGGGUUCUUUUUGUUUAUUUGUUUGUUUGUUUUGUCUUUUCUUUUAGUAUGCCCAGGUAACUUGCAGAACCCGGUCGUUCUUUCUUACUAUAGAUCAGUGAGGUGAAAAGCACUAUCAUUAUUGGAAUGCCCUGUCUCUCCCUUAUACUCUCUUCCUGUCAUCUCCCCUCAGAAGACUUGACACCCCACCCUGGUGCCCUUUCUCUGUACUUUCAUAUGCUCAGCGGCUGUCUUUGCACUUGCUUCAGGAUUGUACCUAACAUUCUGUACUGUAAUGCAUUUUCUUCAGACACUCUUCAGUCAAGUUGUAUUAUAAUUAUGAGUUAAAAUACAUGCAAAGUAAAUAGAGAAAACCUCCAGGGGUUCAUUCCGUAGAGAUAACCAAAGGUUUCAGUUUAAUGUUUUUUUUUUUUUUUUCACACAUGUGCGCUCUCAAAUACAGUCUUUUACAUAUUUUUAAAAAUAAACACUCAAUUUUUUUGGUUUAUUUUCUAGUUUGCAAGAUAUUUCAUUUUUUAAAAUUGUGUUUAUUUACAACCUGCUUUUUUCUAAAAAAGAUUCAAGGUGGGGCCUUCUUUUCUUUUCUUUUUUUUUUUUUUUUUUUGAGAUGAGGUCUUGCUUGUUGCCCAGGCUGGAGUGCAGUGGUGAUCAUAUCUCACUUCAGCCUCUAACUCUAGGCUCAAGCAGUCAUCUCACAUCAGCCUCUGGAGUAGCUGGAACUACAGGUGUGUGCCACCACACCCAGCUACAUUUUUUUUUUUUUUUGAGACAGAGUCUCACUCUGUCACCCAGGCUGGAGUGCAGUGGUGCUAUCUCUGCUCACUGCAGCCUCUGCCUCCUGGGUUCAAGUGAUUCUCCUGUGAAAAUUGCUUCCUUUUCUACACUUGUUCUGUAUUUAUGUUCCUCUGAUGGUCUCCACUUCUAGCCACUUUCUUUUUUUGGCGAUUUAAGUUUUUGGCCCAAAUAGAUAAACAUCUUCUACAUUAUUUUUCUCUUAUUCUCGAUACUGGGUUGCCAUCUUUGGUGAUUUAGUACUUAUUAUGAAAGAGAGAAGCUACACCACUUGAUACCACUUUCAUCUGCAUACUCAUGAUAAUUUGUAUCUUCUGCAGUGAACUCUUAAGUUGAAGAAAUGAAUAAUUUAUAUGUAUAUUUGUAUACUUUUAAAAAUGUAAUUGAAAAAUCCUCUCAUAGUUACUUAACUCCAAGGUUUAAAAAUGCUUCCCAGGGUAAUGAGUUUCUUUAGUCAUGUGACUUUAGAAAUGGGAACCAAAGCUUCCUUAUCUACUUGUGAAAUUCUUGAGUUUUUUCCUUGAACUUCCUUUUUAUCUUCCCUUUGGCUUAUAUAUCUGUGUUUUUUGUUUGUUUUUACUUGCAGCUUUCAAAAGUAGUUUUCAAAGUCAAUGAGAUUGUUUAAAAGAGUAGGUACCUGACAGUCUCUUGCUUGAAUACUAUCUAGUGAGUGAACCAAAUUCCCUGCAACAAUAACCACAACUUUGAAUCAAGAGUUAAAUGAAAAAAGUAACUCCUUCAGCAUUUACUGAGCACCUGCUGGGGCUGAGGAAUGGGGGCAUGUAGAUCUCCCUCUGCUGUCUGGAGCUCCCUUUCUGGUUGGAAAACAUAGAAGCAGCGCAAAAGUUUCACCCAAAACCUUGGCCAUGGUAUGCUAUUGAAACCCCAUAGUUCAGAUUUUAUACUUGAGUUCUUUUCUAAGCCAUGGCUGGAUUAUGUUAAUCUGGCAAAUAAUUAUAAAGCUGGAUUAUUUUAAUCUGGUAAGUAAUUAUAAGGUUGUGCUCCGUGAUGUAGCUAUUAAUAAAAUAUGUGGUAGCACAGACAAGUUGUAUAUAGCACAAAGCUAUACCCCCAGAGGAGACACUAUAUCAGUUGCUGUCUGCCUAGGCUUUCUGUAAACGUGCUGGCUAUCAUUCAGCCUAAAUGUAGAAUGAGUCUAUCCCUUUAACCUGGGCCAUCACCAGGAAUGUAAAGGAACCUAGAACGAGGACCCAGGCAAGAGAUGAGAAACUAGGGGACAGAUGAGUAGGUACCAGGGAUGGUGAUGAGACUGAAGCAAGUGGGGAAUUUUUAUUUUCUUCUCUACUUUUCUCUAUUUUCCAGAUUUUCUUAGAGCAAAAAGCAGGUAGUGCUUUUUACAGAAAAUGAAUGCUAUAUAAAAGUAAUUUUAAGAACUUUAUAUAUCCCUAGUGUUAUGUACAAUUUCUGACUUUGAAUAGAGAUAUCUCCCAAAGGGCCAAGUUUGGCCCUUUAGUUACAAUGGAGAAUCUGUUGUGUAAACUGAGCAAAUACACCUGCCAAGUUGAAAUUUAAUUUAAGCCAAUCUUGUCUAGAUGAACUUAAGAGAACGUCUCCUAAAUAUUUUAUUGCAGUAGUGUAGCAUGAUUGAUAGUAUGCUAUUCUCUUGAAUAGAUGGGGUUGUUUCUUGAGCCACUUUUUAUUCCUUUGAUCAAAACCUUGAGGAGAAGGAAUGCCUGUUUUCCUGACUGCUGUUGCAUGAAGUUAGACAUCCAGUUCCUCUAAAGGUGACAUCAGAUGGUUUAGAUACCUAAAAAGAAGUGAGGCUAAGCCAUAGGUCUUCUUCGUACUACCUGAAGUUGAGACCUGGUCUCUGAACUCAGUUAUUGCUGAAGCAUUAAAAUCUUACAUCUUGCUUAAACUCAGGCAGCUUGACCUGUUCUCAUUUUUCUCUAUCAAAUAAAUUGAAGCCUGGUAAUAAAUUGAUGAUGAGUUCCAAACAUCCCCUUGGUUGGAGACAUUGUAUUCUCCCCACUCACAAUGAGGUCCUGCCAGUUUCCAGAAAAUUUUGCAUGGGGGCUUACCCAUCCUUUUAGAAUCACAUUGCAAGUCACUCUAAAGCAUUAGCAUUGUUAUCUCAUGUAGCUGCAAAAGCUUCCUUUCACAAGCUCUUCUGGAUCCAACAACCAGAUUCCAAGUAUGGUAUCUUAACUACACCACCAGCUCCAUCUUGCUUCAUUGUAUGUUAUGAAGGGAUGAGUAAGCGUUACACAUGGGCUGCAAUGGUCCAAUGAUGACCAGUCUGUUCAAGACCCAAGAGGGCUGAGAUUGGCAGCCCUGGCCAUUGUUUACCACAGCCUAAUGAAGAUGAGUAAAAGCCUAUCUAUCCCCAAGGACCUCCACAUAUGACAGUACUCAACUGAGUCUCACAUAGGAUAGAAUAAGAUAAAAUGCUGGAAGAGAACACAAAUAGUGCUACAAAGCAGGAAGAGAGACUUGAUUUGGGGAUCAAGACAAGCUUAUAGAAGAGACAUCUUGAGAGAGAAGAUAUAAUUUCAGGUACAGACUGAGAGGAGGGAAGGGGCUUUCCAAAUGGAGGCAAAUGCUUGAGUGAAGUUGCUGGGACAGAAAAAUACUGUCCAGGGAACAUUGAGAUAUUUUUGGUUCGGAGUUAGAUUAUGGGUUGGGCUGAAGUGGGGAUGAUACUCUUAGUGCUUGAGCUAUGUAUCAGAAGUUUGUCUAUAGUAUUAUGCACAAUUUCUGAUUUUGAACAGAGCUAUCUCCUGCAGGACCACUCUUGGCCCGUUAGUUACAGUGGGCAAUCCGUUGUGUAAGCUGAGCAAGUAUACCUGCCAAAGUGAAAAUUUAAAUUUAGUUAAGGGCACUACAUCAACUGAUUUAGCUCCCUUGCUCCUGGUGACUUUGCCCAUGUUUCUAUAUCCAAUUAGAUGAUGAUUUAUGAUCUUUUGAUUUAGAUGCUUUCUCAUUUCUGAUUCAUUCUCAUUUUCUGCAGCCUACACAUAAGUGUUAGGAACCAAGGAAGUUAUUGGCGAUAAUGUCUGGUUGGAAUUUGUGGGAGCUUCCUUGAGAGUCAUGAAAAGUCUGUUCUUAGUCUGUUUUGUGCUGCUAUAACAAAAUACCCACAACCAGGUAAUUUAUAAAAAACAAAUUUAUUUCUCACAGUCUGGAGGCUGGGAAGUCCAAGAUCAAGGUGCUGACAUCUGGUGAGGGCUGCUCCCCGCUUCCAAUCUGGUGCCUUGAACACUGCAUUCUACGGAGGGGAGGAAUGCUGUGUCUUAACAUGGCAAAAGGUGGAAGGGCAAAAAGAGAAAUAAACUCCCUUUAUCAGCCCCCUUUAUAAGGGCAUCUAAUCCCAUUCAGGAGGGAGGCGCCUCCAGGGAAUGAUCACCUCUUAAAGGCCCCACUUCUUAAUCCUAUCAUAUUGGCAAUACCUGAACUUUGGAGGGGACACAUUCAAACCAUAGCAGCCUCAUCAAAUAAUUUUAUAAAAUAUGACUUCUAAUUUUAUGUCAUUUUAUAACUGGGAUCAUCUGUUGUUCUGCACGCCAAUGGAGGGGGAAGGUGAAUUUUGUUAUGUUCAAGAUGAAUGCACAAAACUUCUGUGAGAUGGCCACAUUCUACUUUACCCAGAAUUGUGCAACCUCUUCUGCUUUUAGAAACUUCUGGAUGACACUUUGUUUCAUGUUCAUAUCUCCACUGGGGCUUCCCAGACACCUGAAAGUUCAGGUUUGCAUGCUGCUUUCUGCAGCUGGCAAGACAGGUUUCUCCAUUGCCGCCCAGUUUGUGGGGUUGCAAGAAAUUACAUUUGCAUUCACGCUGUGGCUCACUGGACAUGACAUUGCUUUCAUGCCAUACGAUGACCUUGCUUCACUAGAGAAGCAGUAGAAAGAAGGGAAUGUUAAGUACGUCUUUGGAUGGCUUAGCUGGUCAUGCUGCAUGCUUUGCUACUGAUUACAGGGAACAAUAUGUGCCUUUGUUACCAGAUAGUUUGGGGGCAGCGUUGGUGUUCUGUGAGAAAGGUUGAGAGGCCUGACUAAACUUAACCACAUUUGCUGACACCUGGUUAGGGCUAAUGUGGGUACCAGGGAAGUGUGUUAAGUGCUUCAAUAGAGGUGUUUUGUUUUGUUUUGUUUUGUUUUUCGAGACGGAGUUUCACUCUUGUUGCCCAGGCUGGAGUGCAGUGGCGCAAUCUUAGCUCACUGGCAACCUCCACCUCCCAGGCUCAAGAGACUUUUGUGCCUCAACCCCUCGAGUAGCUGGGAUUACAGACAUGCAGCACCACGGCCAGCUAGUUUUUGUAUUUUUAGUAGAGACAGGGUUUUGCCAUGUUGGCCAGGCUGGUCUUGAACUCCUUGCCUCAAGUGAUCCGCCCGCCUUGGCCUCCCAAAGUGCUGGGAUUACAGGUGUGAGCCACCGCGCCUGGCCAGUUCAGGCAUGAACUUUAGAAAUUUCACUUAGAUGGAAGGUAGAUUUGGAGAGGGUGAGGUCUAAAGCAGGGGGAACAGAAUGGCUAGGGGAAUGAGUUUGGAUGAGAGACGGAUGGUAGGCACCAGCAUUUAAGGGACAGGUGCAGAAAGAGUAUGCUGAGGAGUAGAAGAAAGUUAGAGAAGGGUCUGUGUAGAAUAUAGUGGUGUGAGCUCAGCCAAGGGAGAAGAGUUUCAAGGAGGGAUGAAUUAGCAGUGUCAGCUGGAGUUGAGCAGUCAGAUGAAAGAGGACUUCCAAGUUUUUGGAUGUGGCAACCAGGAGGUCACCAGGGCCUCAACAAGAGCUGUGUCAUCAGGGCUGGGAUACUAGCAGGGGCAAACGAGGCACUGGCUUCAGGACAACAUGUGAGGGGGUGCUCAAAAAGUCAGUCAUCAAGAUAGAUAAUAUUUUAAUGCAAUAUUUUAAAAAACAGACAUAAAUGCAAAAAAUCUAUGAUGAACAAAAUACCAACAUUUUAAAUAAAGACAGCGUCAGUAUUGCUGAUUGUCCCUUUUGCCUCAGAUUCCAGUAUGGCUCAGGACUGAGUGUGGCUGUGUAGAGGAGAUGGUGGUGAGGGGAUCCAGGUGGAGGCAUGUUGAGAAGUGAAUUGUGGUUGAAGAAACUGAAGCACUGAGUACAGACUAUUCCUUCAUGAGGUCCCAGCUUUAUGUGAAAGGGAAUAAAGUGAAAGGAUGGUAGGUCUAGGGGACCCUCAGGCUUUUUUGAGGGUUUGGCUUUAUUUUUUAAGAUGGAAGAGACUUGCACAUGUUUACAAGCUGGGAGGAGCCGUCUCUGGAGGUAGAGAGGAUGAAGAGAGUAGACAUAGGGGAUUAGUAGAGACAGGAGGGCACACAGGGAGGCUUAGCCCUAGGCAAGCAGAGGGACAGGAGGGACCAGCUGGGGCAGUGGAAAGGUGGAAGGUGGCAGGAGUUUGUGCCUGAUACAUGGAUGAGAAAUGGCACUGGGGGUGGUGUUGGGAUGGAAGAGAGUUGUGGAGUGUUGGAGGUUUCCCACACUCCUUGAAGGGUGUGGGAAAGGAGCUGAACAGAGUCUUCCUGUAAAUGAAACUGUUGAGCAGCCGUAGGGGCCCAGCUCAGGAAACCACCAGGGUGUGGUGGUGAGUAGUUUUCAGAUUGUGUUAUCUCUUCUCCCUUCCUUCGGAACUUGCUACUGGAGGUGUAGGAGUGGUAGAGGCUUCCUCAUUAAGGCAGGGGUGCUGGAGCGAUCAACCAUCCCUGUUUGCCUGGGACUGAGGGGUUUCCUGGGACUCGGUCACCCUAGAUGUUGCAGGGCUGGCAGUCAGGAGGGAAAAAGGCCAGAUAAUUGAAAAUGCUGGCCAGAGUUUGUAGCAUGCGCUGUCUGAUUGUUGUACCUGAGCGAGUUAGAGAAAACGCCACACUUUGAGAUGAAUUAAGAGUCCGUUUAUUUAGCCGGCGGCCAAGAGACAGCUAACGCUCAAAGUUCUCUCAGCCUCGAAGAAGGGGCUAGAUUUUCUUUUAUACUUUGGUUUAGAAAGGGGAGGGGGGGGUCUAGUUAAAACAAUUUUACAGAAGUAAAGUAGGCAAAAAAGUUAAAAGGAUAAAUGGUUACAGGAAAGUAAACAGUUCCAGGUGCAGGGGCUUUAAGACUAUUACAAGGUGAUAGACGCGGGGCUUUGGGCGUUAUCAAUCUGACGAAUUCCUGAGAACUGCGGAUAUUGCUGGCCACAGUAUCUUAUCAGUUAAUUGCAUUCUUGGAUGUGCUGGGAGUCAGCUUGCACAAGUUAAGUCCUUGCGGAAGGGCUGCCAGUGAAACAGCCAAGAUGGAGUCUGUCUGGCUCUCUUAGCUAAGGGAGAGUCAAUUCAGGUGAAAACAAGGCUAAGUGAUUAAAGGAAAGGGAGAGUCUAAAAACAGCGUUAGUAAAAACAAGGUUGGGCAUUACAUGAUCACUGGGUCUCCACUGUCAGAGGGUCUUUGAGCUCAGUUCUAGUGGCAGCCUCCUGAUCCUCACUUCCCUGGCUGAGGCAAGGUUGUUGCAGCAGCCCCAGGAGUCUUUGUUAGAAUCCCACCCCAGAGCUCCUUCCUCCAGUCCUCUCAGCAGUUUUGUUAGUUCCAGUAUUAAGUGUAAUUUCUACAAAAAAUGCCUGGAAUAUUUCUGUUUCCAGAACCGGAUGCUCCUGUUAGCUAGUGUGUGAAAGAUAACUCUGACUUGCCUAAGCUUUGUUGAUGUUUUGAAUAAUAAUUGGCGAUAGUCUCUUGACUUCUGCAAGAGAAAUGAAACAGAAAUUGGUCUCAAGUUUUAGUUGCUCUUGUGAAGGUCAGGGACAGUUUGUACCAGGGUGUGGGUGUGGAAAAGAAGGGGAGAUAUAGUCAUUAAAUUAGAAUAUGCCUGUGAGGGGAGUUAAGGGGAAUUCCUUUAAAAUUCUAGAAAACACACACAGGUGCCAAUUUUGUCUGGCUAGGGAAAAGUAAACUGCUGAAAACACUUGGGGGGAGAAAUGAAGCUAAUGGUAUCUUGAUCAGUCAGGAGGAUUGGGUAUUUGAAAGCAGGGAAGAAAAAUAAUUGGACUUGGAUAUUCCUUUGCCCCUUCAUCUGAGUAAGGUGAAAGCAAGUGACUCUUCAGAAGAGGCGAAUGGGACACUGAGUCCAGCAGCUCAGGCAGGGUGGAGUUGGUAACUGAUGGGCACAAGUCUUUUACUGGGCUCUAAAGAACUCAUUCAUCUGGGUGUGGUGGCUUACACCUGUAAUCUCAGCAUUUCGGAAGGCUGAGGUAGGAGAAUCACUUGAGCCCAGGAGUUUGAGACCAGCCUGAGAAACACAGUGGGACCCUUUCCCUACAAAAAACUGAAGACCUUAUGAGCUUCCCUAGUCUAAGAGUAAUUUUUAUGUUAAUUUCUUGGCUUGGGCUUAAACCCCAACAAAGUGGUGAUUAUUCGGACCCCAGCCCUACCUCUCCCUAGUAUGCUCUCCUUUCUCAAGUACUCACCACCUCUAGCCACAGUGAACUGCCUCCAGCAUACACACACGCUGCUAUUUUGUUGCAUCUGAGUGGGCUGGCUCCACACGGGAUCUGUAGUUUCCUUUUGAUAUUUUCUUUCAAUGUGCCAGAUGCUACCACUGAGUAAUCUAGAUUUUGCUGCCAAACUCUACCCCCGUUAGCACAGAGGGAAGACAGUAUGCCAGUGCUCUUGCUGAGUGUGCGUGACUGGCAGAAAGCAGUCAUGGGUGUGAUGGUUGGAAGAAACAAACUGAGCAGAUAAUGUUUUUUAAAAUGAUUAUCUCAUUUUGUUAACUCUUGGUGGCAUUGUUAUAUUGUUGAUACUUAUGAAUUACAAAAGUUAGAUGACUGUAAAAAAAUAGAGAAUUAAGCAUUUCAUUUCUAGUAGUUCUGUUUGGUUCUUUUUCAAAUAUGUCAGUGAAUUUGUAUAAUAUCUCAUUUCUUAGUCUUGUGUUUAAUGAUUUUAUUUUUGUGUUUUUAUAAUUCCUUCUACUGCAUAUAUUUUAUACUUUAAUUUAUAAUAACAACUGUUGACAAAAUUGUGACUAUUCAUUAAUACAGUAGAAAAGAACUUGGCCUCCUUUUCAUGGAAGCUGAUGAUGAGAUUAAAGCACUGUUGGCCUGCGAGUGGAGUAUAGAUUUGGGCUGUCCAGAACACAUAAAAUUUGUAUUUAUCUUUCUGAUAAAAAAAAGUAAAAUAGUCUGAGUGCCAAUUUUUCCACUUUCAUUGAGCACAUUUAAUUUUAGUAAAUUUAACUUAGCAAAUUUAAUUUCUCCAGUUAUUUACAAAUAAUCAUAUUUAAGUGAAGUUGGGAUGAAUGGGCAAGCCCAUUUCAAAUUUCUAACCUAAUUUUUCCUCUUGUUUUCAUAUAAAAUUUUUCUAUUUAUGUGUUUUUAUUUUAAGAUAGCUCAAAUCUUUUGUGGACUGAUACUGUAUGUAUAUAAAUAAAUGGAUUCAGUGCUUCUUUCACUAAAUACAGCUAGAUAAAUAUAUAAAUAUACUUGAACACAAAUACAAAGCAACCAUUGGCAAUUUAGAGUUGGGUUGUGUUUCCACUUAUUUUUUGUUAAUAAAUUUGAUUUUAACCUGAAAUAUUGUCUUGUAGGAACAGAUAAAGAACACAAGAGGUGAUUUAACAUAAGUUUUAGCUGUGAAACUUAGAGUAGAUAGGUUAGCAACUUAAAUUUUGAAAGAAAAUAGGAUGAGUUUCAAUGGAAGAAAUUAAGAACACACCCAUUGCAUGAGCUCCUUACCCCUCCUACCCAGCCCCCUCCCAGGAGUGAGAUCUUUCCCCAGAUCCUCUGUAACUUCCAGAUGUUCCACUGAGAACAUCAGAAGCACUAAUGGCAAUUGCUGCCAUGUAGCAGUGCAUUGAGAGUCAGGGCCUCUGGCACCUCCAUGGGGCUCAGGGUCUGAAGACGUGAUCCAAACCUGACAACUUGGUGGCAGGUUCUGUGAGCAUUCAUGAUGUUGUGAAAAGGGCUUGGGGUCUAGGAGGAUGGCAGCAGAGGUUUCUGCCCUCAGGUGUGAGUGAGGGGCUUUUGAAGUAGGAGAGCAACUAGAAAAAAGGAGUGGCACAGGGACAGAAACUUCUUUUCUCCAUUGUUUGUUCAAGGCCACGUGGGUGGAGUCAUUGAGGUGGAGGUUUAACUCUGUGACAUAAGUUUCCCUGAUUUAGUCAGGCUGUCUGUCGUUGGGCUUUUCCCACUUCCUUCUACUACGUACUUCUUCCCUAUUCCUCCUACUGAGGCCAUUAAACCCUUAGUUGUAAUUUUCCCUGAACAUGCUUUACAUUCUGAUGAAUUCUGAAAAAGAAUGUGGGGUUUCCUUGCAGAUGAGUUCAUCUGUUGUUUCAUUUCCUUUACAAUAACUCCCCCACUGGAAAGGAUUCUGAAAGAAAUGAAGUCAGCCCUCAGAAAUGAAGUUGACUGCCUGCUGGCUUUCUGUUGACUGGCCCGGAGCUGUACUGCAAGACCCUUGUGAGCUUCCCUAGUCUAAGAGUAGGAUGUCUGCUGAAGUCAUCCAUCAGGUUGAAGAAGCACUUGAUACAGAUGAGAAGGAGAUGCUGCUCUUUUUGUGCCGGGAUGUUGCUAUAGAUGUGGUUCCACCUAAUGUCAGGGACCUUCUGGAUAUUUUACGGGAAAGAGGUAAGCUGUCUGUCGGGGACUUGGCUGAACUGCUCUACAGAGUGAGGCGAUUUGACCUGCUCAAACGUAUCUUGAAGAUGGACAGAAAAGCUGUGGAGACCCACCUGCUCAGGAACCCUCACCUUGUUUCGGACUAUAGAGUGCUGAUGGCAGAGAUUGGUGAGGAUUUGGAUAAAUCUGAUGUGUCCUCAUUAAUUUUCCUCAUGAAGGAUUACAUGGGCCGAGGCAAGAUAAGCAAGGAGAAGAGUUUCUUGGACCUUGUGGUUGAGUUGGAGAAACUAAAUCUGGUUGCCCCAGAUCAACUGGAUUUAUUAGAAAAAUGCCUAAAGAACAUCCACAGAAUAGACCUGAAGACAAAAAUCCAGAAGUACAAGCAGUCUGUUCAAGGAGCAGGGACAAGUUACAGGAAUGUUCUCCAAGCAGCAAUCCAAAAGAGUCUCAAGGAUCCUUCAAAUAACUUCAGGCUCCAUAAUGGGAGAAGUAAAGAACAAAGACUUAAGGAACAGCUUGGCGCUCAACAAGAACCAGUGAAGAAAUCCAUUCAGGAAUCAGAAGCUUUUUUGCCUCAGAGCAUACCUGAAGAGAGAUACAAGAUGAAGAGCAAGCCCCUAGGAAUCUGCCUGAUAAUCGAUUGCAUUGGCAAUGAGACAGAGCUUCUUCGAGACACCUUCACUUCCCUGGGCUAUGAAGUCCAGAAAUUCUUGCAUCUCAGUAUGCAUGGUAUAUCCCAGAUUCUUGGCCAAUUUGCCUGUAUGCCCGAGCACCGAGACUACGACAGCUUUGUGUGUGUCCUGGUGAGCCGAGGAGGCUCCCAGAGUGUGUAUGGUGUGGAUCAGACUCACUCAGGGCUCCCCCUGCAUCACAUCAGGAGGAUGUUCAUGGGAGAUUCAUGCCCUUAUCUAGCAGGGAAGCCAAAGAUGUUUUUUAUUCAGAACUAUGUGGUGUCAGAGGGCCAGCUGGAGGACAGCAGCCUCUUGGAGGUGGAUGGGCCAGCGAUGAAGAAUGUGGAAUUCAAGGCUCAGAAGCGAGGGCUGUGCACAGUUCACCGAGAAGCUGACUUCUUCUGGAGCCUGUGUACUGCGGACAUGUCCCUGCUGGAGCAGUCUCACAGCUCACCAUCCCUGUACCUGCAGUGCCUCUCCCAGAAACUGAGACAAGAAAGAAAACGCCCACUCCUGGAUCUUCACAUUGAACUCAAUGGCUACAUGUAUGAUUGGAACAGCAGAGUUUCUGCCAAGGAGAAAUAUUAUGUCUGGCUGCAGCACACUCUGAGAAAGAAACUUAUCCUCUCCUACACAUAAGAAACCAAAAGGCUGGGCGUAGUGGCUCACACCUGUAAUCCCAGCACUUUGGGAGGCCAAGGAGGGCAGAUCACUUCAGGUCAGGAGUUCGAGACCAGCCUGGCCAACAUGGUAAACGCUGUCCCUAGUAAAAAUACAAAAAUUAGCUGGGUGUGGGUGUGGGUACCUGUAUUCCCAGUUACUUGGGAGGCUGAGGUGGGAGGAUCUUUUGAACCCAGGAGUUCAGGGUCAUAGCAUGCUGUGAUUGUGCCUACGAAUAGCCACUGCAUACCAACCUGGGCAAUAUAGCAAGAUCCCAUCUCUUUAAAAAAAAAAAAAAAGGACAGGAACUAUCUUACUCAAUGUAUUAGUCAUGUUUCUCUAGAGGGACAGAACUAAUAGGAUACAUGUAUAUAAAAAGGGGAGUUUAUUAAGGAGUAUUGACUCACAUGAUCACAGGGUUAGGUCCCACAAUAGGUCAUCUGCAAGCAAGGAAGCCAAUUCAAGUCCCAAAGCUGAAGAACUUGGAGUCCAAUGUUUGAGGGCAGGAAGCAUUCAGCAUGAGAGAAAGAUGGAGGCCAGAAGACUACACCAGUCUAGUCUUUCCAUGUUUUGCCUGCUUUUAUUCUGGCAGUGCUGGCAGCUGAUUAGAUGGUGCCCACCCAGAUUGAGGAUGGUCUGCCUUUCCCAGUCCACUGACUCAAAUGUUAAAUCUCCUUUGGCAGCACCCUCACAGAUGUACCCGGGAACACUUUGCAUCCUUCUAUUCAAUCAAGUUGAUACUCAGUAUUAACCAUCACAGUCCAUUUGGGCAACUAUACCAAAUUACCAUAGACCAGGUGACUUAAACAGCAGUUAUUUCUCACAGUUCCGGAGGCUGGGAAAUCCAACAUCUAAGUGGUAGCAUAUCUGGUGUCUGGUAAGGCAUGCUUCCAGAUCUUACCAGAUGUCAGUCUUUUGAUGUUCUCACAUGGCAGAAAAAGAGGAUGCAAACUCUCAAGUAUAUCUUUAAGGGCACAAAUUCCAUUCAUGAGGGCUCUACCCUCAUCACCUAAUUACCUCCCAAAGGCCCCACCUUCUGAUACUGUCACUUUGGGGAUACUGUCUCCCCUUUGAAUUCUGGGGGGAAUACAAACAUUCAGUUUGUAACAAUAGCCUUAUGAUUUAGAGGUUACUUGUUCAUUCACCUAGACCUCAAAUUGCAUUUUACAGCUAGUCAAGUAUAUCUUUCUCUGAUUUGAUAGUGUGACCUAAAAGGGGACCAUUGUUUGAAAUAUCAUUAGAGUUGCUUAUUAUUAUUAUUAUUAUUAUUAUUAUUAUUAUUAUUAUUAUUAUUGAGACAGAGUUUCAUUCUGCUGCCCAGGCUGGAGUGCAGUGGCAUCAUCUUGGCUCAUUGCAACCUCUGCCUUCUGGGUUCAAGCGAUUCUCCUGCCUCAGCCUCCCGAGUAGCUGGGAUUACAGGCUCCUGCCACCACACCCGGCUAAUUUUUGUAUUUUUAGUGGAGACAGGGUUUCCACCAUGUUGGCCAGCGUGGUCUUGAACUCCUGACCUCAGGUGAUUCACCAGCCUCGGCCUCCCAAAGUGCUGGGAUUACAGGUGUGAGCCACUGCACCUGGCCUAUUAUUAUUUUUAAAUUUUUUUUUUUUAAUUGAUCAUUCUUGGGUGUUUCUCACAGAGGGUGAUUUGGCAGGGUCACAGGACAAUAGUGGAGGGAAGGUCAGCAGAUAAACAAGUGAACAAAGGUCUCUGGUUUUCCUAGGCAGAGGACCCUGCGGCCUUCCGCAGUGUUUGUGUCCCUGGGUACUUGAGAUUAGGGAGUGGUGAUGACUCUUAAGGAGCAUGCUGCCUUCAAGCAUCUGUUUAACAAAGCACAUCUUGCACUGCCCUUAAUCCAUUUAACCCUGAGUGGACACAGCACAUGUUUCAGAGAGCACAGGGUUGGGGGUAAGGUCAUAGAUCAACAGCAUCCUAAGGCAGAAGAAUUUUUCUUAGUACAGAACAAAAUGAAGUCUCCCAUGUCUACUUCUUUCUACACAGACACAGCAACAAUCUGAUUUCUCUAUCUUUUCCCCACCUUUCCCCCUUUUCUAUUCCACAAAACCGCCAUCGUCAUCAUGGCCUGUUCUCAAUGAGCUGUUGGGUACACCUCCCAGACGGGGUGGCGGCUGGGCAGAGGGGCUCCUCACUUCCCAGAUGGGGCGGCCAGGCGGACGCGCCCCCCACCUCCCUCCCGGACGGGAUAGCUGGCCGGGCGGGGGCUGACCCCCCACCUCCCUCCCCGACGGGGCGGCUGGCCGGGCGGGGGCUGACCCCCACGCCUCCCUCCCGGACGGGGCGGCUGCCAGGCGGAGGGGCUCCUCACUUCUCAGACGGGGUGGCUGCUGGGCGGAGACGCUCCUCACUUCCCAGACAGGGUGGCUGUCGGGCGGAGGGGCUCCUCACUUCUCAGACGGGGCAGCUGCGGGCGGAGGGGCUCCUCACUUCUCAGACGGGGUGGCCGGGCAGAGAAGCUCCUCACAUCCCAGACGGGGGGGCGGGGCAGAGGCGCUCCCCACAUCUCAGACGAUGGGCGGCCGGGCAGAGACGCUCCUCACUUCAUCCCAGACGGGGUGGCGGCCGGGCAGAAGCUGUAAUCUCGGCACCCUGGGGGGCCAAGGCAGGCGGCUGGGAGGCGGAGGCCGUAGCCAGCUGAGAUCACACCACUGCACUCCAGCCUGGGCAACAUUGAGCACUGAGUGGACGAGACUCUGCCCGCAAUCCCGGCACCUCGGGAGGCCGAGGCUGGCAGAUCACUCGCAGUCAGGAGCUGGAGACCAGCCCGGCCAACACAGUGAAACCCUGUCUCCACCAAAAAAAUACGAAAACCAGUCAGGCGUGGCGGCGCCCGCAAUGGCAGGCACGCGGCAGGCCGAGGCGGGAGAAUCAGGCAGGGAGGCUGCAGUGAGCCGAGAUGGCAGCAGUACAGUCCAGCUUCGGCUCGGCAUCAGAGGGAGACCGUGGGGAGAGGGAGAAGAGAGGGAGGGGGAGAGGGCUAUUUUUAAAAUUUUUUAAAAUUGCUGAACAGGGGUACCUCUGGGCAGUGUGUCAGAAUACCACUUUUUAAAUAUUUUAUGAUUUAUUUAUUUUUCUAUUUCUUGAGGUUUUAACUGAUGUGUAUCUGUAUGUCUAUUUGUGUAUAUUUUGUCAUGAUCAUGUAACAGAGUCUGAAAAGUGUCGAAGAGACAGUUUUCAGGAACAACAAGCAAUUAUUCCUACUUUCCAAGUUAUUUUGAUGCCAUGGUGGCUCAUACCUAUAAUCUGAGUACUUUGGGAGGCUGAGGUGGACUGAUCACUUGAGCCCAGGAGUUUGAGACCAGCCUGGGCAACAUAGCAAGACUCCAUCUCUACAAAAAAAGACAAAAUUUAGCUGAGCGUGGUGGCGUGUUCCUGUAGUCCCAGCUACUUGGGAGGCUGAAGUGAGUGGAUCCCCUGAGCCCAGAGAGGUCAAGGUUGUGAUGAGCUGUGAUCACACCACUGCACUUCAGCAUGGGAGACAGAGUGAGACCCUGUUUCAGAAAAAAUAAAUAAAUAAAACCACCAGCACCACAAACAACAACAAAAAGUUAUUUUGUACUUGUUUUGAGCACAGGACUCCUGAGGGUAUCUUUGCAUUUAAUAUUACAUAGGGGUGCCAGUGGGAAGUAAUGUGUAUGCUUGGCCUCAUGAGCUAAAACCCUGUGUUAAUUAUGACAGAAGGAAAGUGUGUGAGAGAGAUCUUAACUACCUAGCAGCUCUAGCUGCCAUCUUGAACCAUGAAGAUACGGGCCACACGUAGGGGUAGCUGGGUAGUGAGCAGCAAGAAGCCUUGUUGGAUGAGGGCACGAAGGAGCAGAAUCACUGGAAUCACUGUGUCAGCCCUAAUUACCUACCUCUGGACUUUUAUGUGAGGGGAAAAAAAAUUGACAGUUUAUAUUUAUCUCAACCUAGUUAACCCAAGUGAUGCAUUGUUAUGAGAUUAAAAUGUUUGGAGGCCGGGUGCGGUGGCUCACGCCUAUAAUCCCAGCCCUUUGGGAGGCCAAGGCGGGCGGAUCACGAGGUCAGGAGAUCAAGACCAUCCUGGCUAACAUGUAAAACCCCGUCUCUACUAAAAAUACAAAAAAUUAGCCAGGCGUUGUGGCGGUCGCCUGUAGUCCCUGCUAUUUGGGAGGCCGAGGCAAGAGAACGGCAUGAACCUGGGAGGUGGAGCUUGCAGCGAGCUGAGAUCUUGCCACUGCACUCCAGCCUGGGCGACAGUGCGAGACUCUGUCUCAAAAAUAAAUAAAUAAAUAAAUAAUAAAUAAAAUGUUUGGAAUGUUGGCUUCAUCCCUGGGAUGCAAGGCUGGUUCAACAUACGCAAAUCAAGAAACAUAAUUCAUCACAUAAACAGAACUAAAGACAAAAACCACAUGAUUAUCUCAAUAGAUACAGAAAAGGCCUUCAAUAAAAUUCAACGUUGCUUCAUGUUAAAAACUCUCAAUAAACUAGGUAUUGAUGGAAAAUAUCUCAAAAUAAUAACCAUUUAUGACAAACCCACAGCCAUUAUCAUACUGAAUGGGCAAAAGCUGGAAGCAUUCCCCUUGAAAACUGGCACAAGACAGGGAUGCCGUCUCACCACUCCUAUUUAACAUAGUAUUGGAAGUUCUGGCCAAGAAAAUCAGGCAAGAGAAACAAAUAAGGGGUAUUCAAAUAGGAAAAGAGGAAGUAAAACUGUGUUUGCAGAUGACAUGAUACUAUAUCUAGAAAACCCCAUUAUCUCCACCCAAAAGUUCCUUAAGCUGAUAAGCAACUUCAGCAAAGUCUCAGGAUACAAAAUCAAUGUGCAGAAAUCACAAGCAUUCUAUACACCAACAAUACACAAGCAGAGAGCCAAAUCAUGAAUGAACUCCCAUUCACAGUUGCUAGAAAGAGAAUAAAAUACCUAGGAAUACAGCUAAUAAGAUGUGAAGGAUCUCUUCAAGGAGAACUACAAACCACUGCUCAAGGAAAUAAGAGAGGACACAAAUGAAAAAACAUUCCAUUCUCGUGGAUAGGAAGAAUCAAUAUCAUGAAAAUGGCCAUACUACCCAAAGUAAUUUAUAGGUUCAUUGCUAUUCCCAUUAAACUACUAUUGACAUUCUUCACAGAAUUAGAAAAAAACUACUUUAAAAUUCAAAUGGAACCAAAAAAGAGCCCGUAUAACCAAGACAACAAUAAGCAAAAAGAACAAAGCUGGAAGCAUCACACUACCCAACUUCAAAGUAUACUGCAAGGCUACAGUAGCCAAAAUGGCAUGGUACUGGUACAAAAACAGACACAUAGACCAAUGGAACAGAAUAGAGACCAGAGAAAGAAGACCACACAUCUACAGCCAUCUGAUCAUCGACAAACCUGACAAAAACAAGCAAUGGGGAAAAGAUUCCCUAUUUAAUAAAUGGUGCUGGGAAAACUGGCUAGCCAUAUGCAGAAAAUUGAAACUGACCCCUUCCUUACACCUUAUACAAAAAUUAACUCAAGAUUAAAGACUUAAUGUAAAACCUAAAACUAUAAAAACCCUAGAAGAAAAUCUAUUUAAUACCAUUCAAGACAUAGGCACAAGCAAAGGUUUCAUGACAAAAACAUCAAAAGCAAUUGCAACAAAAGCAAAAAUUACAAAUGGGAUCUAAUUAAACUAAAGAGCUCCUGCACAGCAAAAGAAACUAUCAUUAGAGUGAACAGGCAACCUACAGAAUGGGAGAACAUUUUUGCAAUCUAUCCAUCUGACAAAGGUCUAAUAUCCAGAACCUACAAGGAACUUAAAACAAAUUUACAAGGAAAAAAACAACCCCAUCAAAAAGUGGACAAAGGACAUGAACAGACACUUCUCAAAAGAAGACAUUUAUGUGGCCAACAAACAUAUAAAAAAAAGCUCAACCUUACUGAUCAUUAGAGAAAUGCAAAGGAGAACCACAAUGAGAUACCAUCUCAUGCCGGUCAGAAUGGUGAUUAUUAAAAAGUCAAAAAACAACAGAUGCUGGCGAGGCUGUGGAGAAGUAGGAACACUUUUACAUUGUUGGUGGGAAUGUAAAUUAGUUCAACCGUUGUGGAAGUGUGUGUGGCUAUUCCUCAAAGAUCUAGAACUAGAAAUACUAUUUGUCCCAGCAAUCCCAUUACUGGGUAUAUACCCAAAGGAAUAUAAACCAUUUUAUUAUAAAGAUACAUGCACAUUUUUGUUCAUUGCAGCACUCUUCACAAUAGCAAAGACACAAUAGCAAAUGCCCAUCAAAGAUAGACUGGAUAAAGAAAAUGUGGUACAUAUACACCAUGGAAUACUGUGCAGUGCAGCCAUUACAGCUUUUGGUGAUACAGUGAAUCAGAUUUUUCAUUAAUUCUUUUAAUUGGUUAUUACUGAACGUGAAAAAGUAAUGUUUGUAUUGAAAUCUUGAGUCUGGCCAUGUUUCUAUUUUAAAUUCAUAAAGAAUUCUAACAAGAGGAAUUCCAAGAAUGUCAUAAAUGGAUGUUUCUCCAUGGAUGAAGGAACUGUUUUAUUCACUUGCUGAUAAUUCAGCCUAAUCCAGUUUGACAUCAUAUAGAUAAGUAGUUGAAUUAUGGAUUUAAAAUACAUAUCAUUUUCUAACUCCAAAGGUAAUACUUAUUUAAAUGGUUUUGAAAAUAUAGAAAGGCACAAUUUCUUUUUAAAUCUGUUAUUCUCCACCACCACUCAAUCUGUCUAUCAUCUAUCUCUCCAUUCAUUCUUCCAUUUGUUUAUAUCUGUUAAUCUUUGUAUGUGUUCAUGUAUAGCUUUUACAUGAUUGGAAUCAUAAUGCAUAUUCCAUUUUGAAGUCUGCUUUUUUUUACACAAAAAUAUGUUGUGAAUAUUUUCCUAUAUUAUGAAAUAUCAUUAGCUGAGCUUUUAGAAUUGACUGCAUGUUUUGGUACCAUUUAGAUAUAGUUUAAGAUACUUAGAAGUUAUGUGGCUUUGCCACUAUGGAUGAAUCUUAUUUACUCAAUAUUAAUUACUUACAAAUAACCUCACCUAAACACUACUCAGCCAUAAAAAGGAAUGAAUUAAUGACAUUCACAGCAACCUGGAGACUAUUACUCUAAAGGAAGUAACUGAGGAAUGGAAAACCAAACAUUGUAUGUUCUCACUCAUAAGUGGGAGAUAAGCUAUGAGGAUGCAAAGGCAUAAGAAGGAUACAAUGGACUUUGGGGACUUAGGGGAAAGGGUGGGAGGGGGGUGAAGGAUAAAAGAAUACAAAUUGGGUUCAGUGUAUACUGCUCAGGUGAUGGGUGCACCAGAAUCUCACAAGUAACCACUUAAUUACUUACGCAUGUAACCAGAUACCACCUGUUCCCCAAACACCUAUGGAAAUAAUUUUGUUUUUUUUUUUAAAAAAGGAAUGAGAUCAUGUCCUUUGCAGGGACAUGGAUGAAGCUGGAAGCCAUUAUCCUCAGCAAACUAACAGAGGAGCAGGAAACCAAACACCACAUGUUCUCACUUGUAAGCGGAAGCUGAACAAUGAGAACACACGGACACAGGGAUGAGAUCAACACACACUGGGGCCUGAUGCAGGGGCCGUAGCGGGGAGAGCAUCAGGAUAACUAGCUAAUGCAUGUGGGGCUUAAUACCUAGGUGAUAGGUUGAUAGGUGCAGCAAACCACCAUGGGACACGUUUACCUAUGUAACAAACCCGCACAUCCUGCACUUGUAUCCAGAACUUAAAAUAUUUUAAAAAUCUUUAGAGAAUACAAAAAAAAAAAAAAAGAUUCUUCAAUGCAUACACAAUAAAAUUGCAGUUCAGUCAAACAUUGGAAGUCUUUCUCUGACUGUCUAGUUGGUAUCUUCAUUUUCAGCUUCUUCAAGAUCCCACUCCAAACACUGUUAGCUCAGCCAAAUUGAACAGCUCAUAUCUCCUACCUCUGGAUCUUUGGUUCUGGUGAUUGUAUAUUUCUGGACCAUCUGGAACCCCAGCAUAUCACCCUACCCCACAUCUCCACAUCCCCAAAAUAUAACCAUACUUCAAGGGCAGUUCAAAUACCAUCUCCUUCUAUCCUCCAUGAAGUCAGUUAUCUCUUCCAUUGGAAUUAUCGCCCCCUCUCCUGAACAGUACUAUUUCGUGUGAAUCUCCUCCAAGCCUUCUUUUCAUUUUAUAUCUCAUGCUGUAAUUCUUGGAAAGUAUGCUGUAGCUCAAGUGCAGAAUUCUCAUCAGUUUUAUCUUUAUAUCUCUCCUAAACACUUUACCUGAUGAAGAGCCUGGCAUACACAUAAAUAUAUAUUGAAUGAAUCAGUGAUGGAUUGAAAAGAGAAAUGAUGGAUCUCCUAAAUUUUAACUUUUAUAAAAUAUUUUGAUACAUUCAUGACCUUACUUUAGCAAGCAAUGAACGUGAUGUAAACUAUUGUUGAUAUAGUUUUUAUAUUGGAAGUGUAAGUAGUUUGUGGCAUGGGAUUGUGACAUAUCCUAGGUUUCCUCAUCUUCUUUUUAUUGAAAUGUAAUUCACAAGCCAUAAAAUUUGCCCCUUUAAAGUAAAUGAUGCAGUGGAUUUUAGUAUAUUUACAGAGUUGUGCAAUCAUCACCACUAUCUAAUUCCAGAACAUUUCCAUCUACCUAGAAACUCCAUACCAGUGAGCUGCCACUCUAAUCCUCCUCUUCCCCCAGCCUCUAGAAACAAUAAUCCAUUUUCUGUCUCUAUGAUUUGCCUGUUCUAGAUAUUUUAUAAAAAUAAACAUGUGGCCUUUCGUGUCUGACUUCCUUCACUUA